GCGUUCCCGGCCCGGAUAUCUCUGCUCUAGGAGCUGUGGCCCGUGGGCAACCGCGGCUUUCUGGAGCGCGCGCCCGUGACGACCCCCAGUUUUGGGGCGCGCGCUCUGAUAUCGGGUGGCGGUGCUGCCUCGAGAGCGCGCAGGAGGCUUCUGCUGAGCAGAGGGCCGGCCGCGGCUCGUUGCGCUGGGAAGGUUGAGGAUUGGGUCCUUUCUGGUCUGGUGACGUUCCCGGGCAUCCGUGGCCUCGGCCUGGAGAGAAACCAACCAGCUUUGCUGUCUGGCUUGCGGUUCCGCUCCUCUGUGAGGGGGGCGAGAUUGCCCGUUCUCCUCGAAGAAUGCCGUUACUUGAGGCCCAAGUACGGUGCGGGUGCUUGGGUAGGGUGUUUCUCUGCUUCGGAAACCAAGCCCUCUUGGUUUGAGAGGGCAGUGAGCCCCUUCGGAUUUCCUCACCUUGUACUGGGCUUUCUGCCGGGCAGGGAAGGUUAAUAUUAGAAGGCCCUUGAGUGGUACCUGCUUAUCUUUCAUUAGAAACUAAUACGUCCAUAAGCGUAAUUCAUACACGUCACCUCUGUGCGCUCCGGAAGGGAAUUCGCUUAUGUGGCCCAUGUGAACUCCGAGCUCUAAAAUGCCAGUUUAAAUCCUUAAACGCAGCUUUUCUUUUGCAAUAUUAGAAGUCUUAAGAACUCAGGACAAGCAGCAGAAAUACAUGCAACAUGGUGACUGGAACCCUAAGGACUCUGCAAUAUGAAUAAUUCCCUAGAGAACACCAUCUCCUUUGAAGAGUACAUCCGAGUAAAGGCACGGUCUGUCCCGCAACACAGGAUGAAGGAAUUUCUGGACUCACUGGCCUCUAAGGGGCCAGAAGCCCUUCAGGAGUUCCAGCAGACAGCCACCACUACCAUGGUGUACCAACAGGGUGGGAACUGCAUAUACACAGACAGCACUGAAGUGGCUGGGUCUUUGCUUGAACUUGCCUGUCCAGUCACCACCAGUGUUCAGCCACAAACCCAGCAAGAACAGCAGAUCCAGGUUCAGCAGCCGCAGCAGGUUCAGGUCCAGGUGCAGGUACAGCAGUCUCCGCAACAGGUCUCGGCUCAGCUCUCCCCACAACUCACCGUUCACCAGCCUACUGAGCAACCCAUCCAGGUCCAGGUGCAGAUCCAAGGCCAGGCACCACAGUCAGCAGCCCCCUCCAUUCAGACCCCGUCUCUGCAGAGUCCCAGUCCCUCGCAGCUGCAAGCAGCUCAGAUCCAGGUGCAGCACGUGCAAGCAGCCCAGCAGAUCCAGGCUGCAGAAAUCCCGGAGGAGCACAUCCCACAUCAGCAAAUCCAGGCUCAGCUGGUGGCUGGCCAGUCUCUUGCUGGUGGUCAGCAGAUCCAAAUCCAGACCGUGGGUGCCCUUUCCCCACCACCAUCCCAGCAGGGCUCACCCCGGGAAGGGGAGCGGCGGGUUGGCACGGCCAGUGUCCUCCAACCAGUGAAGAAGCGCAAAGUGGACAUGCCCAUCACUGUGUCCUACGCCAUCUCAGGGCAGCCGGUGGCCACCGUGCUGGCCAUUCCACAGGGCCAGCAGCAGAGUUAUGUGUCUUUGAGGCCAGACUUACUGACAGUAGACAGUGCCCACCUGUACAGUGCCACUGGGACCAUUACUAGCCCUACAGGAGAAACCUGGACCAUCCCUGUUUAUUCUGCCCAGCCCCGGGGGGACCCUCAGCAGCAGAGCAUUACCCACAUUGCCAUUCCCCAGGAAGCCUACAACGCAGUUCACGUCAGUGGCUCACCCACAGCCCUGGCAGCUGUUAAGCUGGAGGAUGACAAGGAGAAGAUGGUGGGCACCACAUCUGUAGUGAAAAACUCCCAUGAAGAGGUAGUGCAGACCCUUGCAAACUCUCUCUUUCCAGCACAGUUCAUGAAUGGCAACAUCCACAUUCCAGUGGCUGUGCAGGCUGUGGCAGGCACGUACCAGAAUACGGCUCAAACUGUCCAUAUAUGGGACCCCCAACAGCAGCCGCAGCAGCAAACUCCCCAGGAACAGACACCACCACCACAGCAGCAGCAGCAGCAACUCCAAGUUACUUGUUCAGCUCAAACUGUCCAGGUUGCUGAAGUUGAACCACAGUCACAGCCACAGCCUUCCCCAGAACUUCUGCUUCCAAAUUCUUUGAAGCCAGAAGAAGGGCUUGAAGUAUGGAAAAACUGGGCCCAGACCAAGAAUGCUGAACUAGAGAAGGAUGCUCAGAACAGAUUGGCACCCAUUGGGAGGCGCCAACUGCUGCGAUUCCAGGAAGAUCUCAUCUCCUCUGCUGUGGCAGAGUUGAAUUAUGGGCUCUGUCUAAUGACACGGGAAGCUCGAAAUGGAGAAGGUGAACCCUAUGACCCAGAUGUGCUCUACUAUAUUUUCCUGUGUAUUCAAAAGUAUCUUUUUGAAAAUGGAAGGGUAGAUGACAUUUUCUCCGAUCUUUAUUAUGUUCGGUUCACGGAGUGGCUACAUGAAGUUCUGAAGGAUGUUCAGCCCCGGGUCACUCCACUUGGCUAUGUCUUGCCCAGCCACGUGACUGAGGAGAUGCUAUGGGAGUGCAAGCAGCUUGGGGCUCACUCCCCCUCCACCUUGCUGACCACCCUCAUGUUCUUUAAUACCAAGUACUUCCUAUUGAAGACAGUGGACCAGCACAUGAAGCUGGCCUUCUCCAAGGUCUUGCGACAGACAAAGAAGAACCCCUCUAAUCCCAAGGAUAAAAGCACGAGUAUCCGGUACUUGAAGGCCCUUGGAAUACACCAGACUGGCCAGAAAGUUACAGAUGACAUGUAUGCAGAACAGACGGAAAAUCCAGAGAAUCCAUUGAGAUGUCCCAUCAAGCUCUAUGAUUUCUACCUCUUCAAAUGCCCCCAGAGUGUGAAAGGCCGGAAUGACACCUUUUACCUGACACCUGAGCCAGUGGUGGCCCCCAACAGCCCAAUCUGGUACUCAGUCCAGCCUAUCAGCAGAGAGCAGAUGGGACAAAUGCUGACGCGGAUCCUGGUGAUAAGAGAAAUUCAGGAGGCCAUCGCAGUGGCCAAUGCAAGCACUAUGCACUGAGAUGCCUUGGCCAUGGCACAAGAGAAACCAGCCAGGAAAAACCAGACAGACUUUCACACUAAAGAAGAGGCCUCCAUUUUUUUUUUUCUUUUUUUUAUUGGUGUAGUUACGAAGCCUUUCAGGCUGCUUCUGUUUAAAAUAUAAAAGAAAACUUUGCCCCCUUUGCAUCUUCAUAAACCUGCUGCGGCAGACUCCUCAGCCGAUGGUGGCUCUGGGUUUCCUUGAGUGUCAUAUGUCCUAGAAAGUUGCUGGCUGACUCUUUUUUGUCUGGGGCCUGGGGAAAGGGCUUGGACUGUGAAAAGAAAUGUGGCCCCUUUCCAUCUUCAAGAGAGAUGGAAUUAAUGAUGGAUGGACCCUGGAGGGAAUCUCCCCAGCCGACUUCCACUGGGCUGACAGACUUUGCUGACCACAGGGGAACGAUGUUCUUUUCUUUCUUCAUGAUCAGACAUAAACUUAGCAUCUUAAUGGAAGAAAAAUGAGGGGAACUUCAAUUAUGAUUUAUUAAAGACAAUUUCUAUUACACCCUCCUUUAUGACAAGUGACAUUUUAGAUGUAAAAGUAAAAACUUUACCAUGCCUUUUUUUUUUUUGUUGGCCUAACAUUGAGGCCUUAAAACCUGAGGCUCCUGUGCCUGAUGGAAUUCUUGUAACAUACACUUGUGUAUCAUAUAAAGAUACCACUCUGUUUCUCUUAUGUAUUCUUACUCUAGUUGUUUAUUAAGAAUGACAAGCACGUCUUUUCAACA